GCAGCUUGAUGGCGUCGGGCUGGAGAGCCGCAGUCCCGGCUGCAGCACCUGGGAGAAGGCAGACCGUGUGAGGGGGCCUGUGGCCCCAGCGUGCUGUGGCCUCGGGGAGUGGGAAGUGGAGGCAGGAGCCUUCCUUACACUUCGCCAUGAGUUUCCUCAUCGACUCCAGCAUCAUGAUUACCUCCCAGCAGAUAACCUUGCCUCGUACUUACUCAACAAAAGUGAAGCCAAAAGAUACUAUUUUUUGGAUUUGGGUGGCUUUUCUUCAUGCGCCAAUUGUUUAAAGACUAUGAGAUACGUCAGUAUGUUGUACAGGUGAUCUUCUCCGUGACGUUUGCAUUUUCUUGCACCAUGUUUGAGCUCAUCAUCUUUGAAAUCUUAGGAGUAUUGAAUAGCAGCUCCCGUUAUUUUCACUGGAAAAUGAACCUGUGUGUAAUUCUGCUGAUCCUGGUUUUCAUGGUGCCUUUUUACAUUGGCUAUUUUAUUGUGAGCAAUAUCCGACUACUGCAUAAACAACGACUGCUUUUUUCCUGUCUCUUAUGGCUGACCUUUAUGUAUUUCUUCUGGAAACUAGGAGAUCCCUUUCCCAUUCUCAGCCCAAAACAUGGGAUCUUAUCCAUAGAACAGCUCAUCAGCCGGGUUGGUGUGAUUGGAGUGACUCUCAUGGCUCUUCUUUCUGGAUUUGGUGCUGUCAACUGCCCAUACACUUACAUGUCUUACUUCCUCAGGAAUGUGACUGACACGGAUAUUCUAGCCCUGGAACGGCGACUGCUGCAAACCAUGGAUAUGAUCAUAAGCAAAAAGAAAAGGAUGGCAAUGGCACGGAGAACAAUGUUCCAGAAGGGGGAAGUGCAUAACAAACCAUCAGGUUUCUGGGGAAUGAUAAAAAGUGUUACCACUUCAGCAUCAGGAAGUGAAAAUCUUACUCUUAUUCAACAGGAAGUGGAUGCUUUGGAAGAAUUAAGCAGGCAGCUUUUUCUGGAAACAGCUGAUCUAUAUGCUACCAAGGAGAGAAUAGAAUACUCCAAAACCUUCAAGGGGAAAUAUUUUAAUUUUCUUGGUUACUUUUUCUCUAUUUACUGUGUUUGGAAAAUUUUCAUGGCUACCAUCAAUAUUGUUUUUGAUCGAGUUGGGAAAACGGAUCCUGUCACAAGAGGCAUUGAGAUCACUGUGAAUUAUCUGGGAAUCCAAUUUGAUGUGAAGUUUUGGUCCCAACACAUUUCCUUCAUUCUUGUUGGAAUAAUCAUCGUCACAUCCAUCAGAGGAUUGCUGAUCACUCUUACCAAGUUCUUUUAUGCCAUCUCUAGCAGUAAGUCCUCCAAUGUCAUUGUCCUGCUAUUAGCACAGAUAAUGGGCAUGUACUUUGUCUCCUCUGUGCUGCUGAUCCGAAUGAGUAUGCCUUUAGAAUACCGCACCAUAAUCACUGAAGUCCUUGGAGAACUGCAGUUCAACUUCUAUCACCGUUGGUUUGAUGUGAUCUUCCUGGUCAGCGCUCUCUCUAGCAUACUCUUCCUCUAUUUGGCUCACAAACAGGCACCAGAGAAGCAAAUGGCACCUUGAACUUAAGCCUACUACAGACUGUUAGAGGCCAGUGGUUUCAAAAUUUAGAUAUAAGAGGGGGGAAAAAUGGAACCAGGGCCUGACAUUUUAUAAACAAACAAAAUGCUAUGGUAGCAUUUUUCACCUUCAUAGCAUACUCCUUCCCCGUCAGGUGAUACUAUGACCAUGAGUAGCAUCAGCCAGAACAUGAGAGGGAGAACUAACUCAAGACAAUACUCAGCAGAGAGCAUCCCGUGUGGAUAUGAGGCUGGUGUAGAGGCGGAGAGGAGCCAAGAAACUAAAGGUGAAAAAUACACUGGAACUCUGGGGCAAGACAUGUCUAUGGUAGCUGAGCCAAACACGUAGGAUUUCCGUUUUAAGGUUCACAUGGAAAAGGUUAUAGCUUUGCCUUGAGAUUGACUCAUUAAAAUCAGAGACUGUAACACUUUUGCCUUACGUUCAUUUUAUCAAGCAUAGCUUGGUAUUUAUUAUGCUUGUGUGAUCUAACAUCAGUUAGCAUCCCACACCUCCUCAUCUGAUCCUGCCCCAUUAAAAUAACCAAGAAAGAGGUUAUCUGUUCUUUUCCGGGAAAGGGGUGGUAUGCACCUGAAAUAGAUUUUACCAAAAGAGA